AGUGCUGAGCUUGGUGUCCCACCGCCACAAGGAGGCAGGGAAGAAACCCACUAGUCCCAGCUCCUGGGGUGGCACAGACAUUGCAACUGGCCCUGCCUGUGGGUCCUAGGGGCCCUUGGCUACCAGGAGGCUAAGAACACUGCUCAUGAAUGACAGUGAGCCCUGAAAGCUCUGGGGGUGUCACCCAGUCCCACAAGCCUGCAUCCCCUGCAGUGGAGAUGGGCUCAGCUCCUGGACGUGCCACAGACAGAAAGCAUAACAUACACUCGCCAGGAAGAGCCUUUGCCUGACUCAGGGCAGCUCAGAGUGUGGGGCAGAAGGUGACCAGCCAGCUCAGGGCAGGAGAUGCAGAGCACAGCCAAUUACCUGUGGCACACAGAUGACCUGCUGGGGCAGGGGGCCACUGCCAGUGUGUACAAGGCCCGCAACAAGAAAUCCGGAGAGCUGGUUGCUGUGAAGGUCUUCAACACUACCAGCUACCUGCGGCCCCGCGAGGUGCAGGUGAGGGAGUUUGAGGUCCUGCGGAAGCUGAACCACCAGAACAUUGUCAAGCUCUUUGCGGUGGAGGAGACGGGCGGAAGCCGGCAGAAGGUACUGGUGAUGGAGUACUGCUCCAGUGGGAGCCUGCUGAGUGUGCUGGAGAGCCCUGAGAAUGCCUUUGGGCUGCCUGAGGAUGAGUUCCUGGUGGUGCUGCGCUGUGUGGUGGCCGGCAUGAACCACCUGCGGGAGAACGGCAUUGUGCAUCGCGACAUCAAGCCGGGGAACAUCAUGCGCCUCGUAGGGGAGGAGGGGCAGAGCAUCUACAAGCUGACAGACUUCGGCGCUGCCCGGGAGCUGGAUGAUGAUGAGAAGUUCGUCUCGGUCUAUGGGACUGAGGAGUACCUGCAUCCCGACAUGUAUGAGCGGGCGGUGCUUCGAAAGCCCCAGCAAAAAGCGUUCGGGGUGACUGUGGAUCUCUGGAGCAUUGGAGUGACCUUGUACCAUGCAGCCACUGGCAGCCUGCCCUUCAUCCCCUUUGGUGGGCCACGGCGGAACAAGGAGAUCAUGUACCGGAUCACCACGGAGAAGCCGGCUGGGGCCAUUGCAGGUGCCCAGAGGCGGGAGAACGGGCCCCUGGAGUGGAGCUACACCCUCCCCAUCACCUGCCAGCUGUCACUGGGGCUGCAGAGCCAGCUGGUGCCCAUCCUGGCCAACAUCCUGGAGGUGGAGCAGGCCAAGUGCUGGGGCUUCGACCAGUUCUUUGCGGAGACCAGUGACAUCCUGCAGCGAGUUGUCGUCCAUGUCUUCUCCCUGUCCCAGGCAGUCCUGCACCACAUCUAUAUCCAUGCCCACAACACGAUAGCCAUUUUCCAGGAGGCCGUGCACAAGCAGACCAGUGUGGCCCCCCGACACCAGGAGUACCUCUUUGAGGGUCACCUCUGUGUCCUCGAGCCCAGCGUCUCAGCACAGCACAUCGCCCACACGACGGCAAGCAGCCCCCUGACCCUCUUCAGCACAGCCAUCCCUAAGGGGCUGGCCUUCAGGGACCCUGCUCUGGACGUCCCCAAGUUCGUCCCCAAAGUGGACCUGCAGGCGGAUUACAACACUGCCAAGGGCGUGUUGGGCGCCGGCUACCAGGCCCUGCGGCUGGCACGGGCCCUGCUGGAUGGGCAGGAGCUAAUGUUUCGGGGGCUGCACUGGGUCAUGGAGGUGCUCCAGGCCACAUGCAGACGGACUCUGGAAGUGGCAAGGACAUCCCUCCUCUACCUCAGCAGCAGCCUGGGAACUGAGAGGUUCAGCAGCGUGGCUGGAACGCCUGAGAUCCAGGAACUGAAGGCGGCUGCAGAACUGAGGUCCAGGCUGCGGACUCUAGCGGAGGUCCUCUCCAGAUGCUCCCAAAAUAUCACGGAGACCCAGGAGAGCCUGAGCAGCCUGAACCGGGAGCUGGUGAAGAGCCGGGAUCAGGUACAUGAGGACAGAAGCAUCCAGCAGAUUCAGUGCUGUUUGGACAAGAUGAACUUCAUCUACAAACAGUUCAAGAAGUCUAGGAUGAGGCCAGGGCUUGGCUACAACGAGGAGCAGAUUCACAAGCUGGAUAAGGUGAAUUUCAGUCAUUUAGCCAAAAGACUCCUGCAGGUGUUCCAGGAGGAGUGCGUGCAGAAGUAUCAAGCGUCCUUAGUCACACACGGCAAGAGGAUGAGGGUGGUGCACGAGACCAGGAACCACCUGCGCCUGGUUGGCUGUUCUGUGGCUGCCUGUAACACAGAAGCCCAGGGGGUCCAGGAGAGUCUCAGCAAGCUCCUGGAAGAGCUAUCUCACCAGCUCCUUCAGGACCGAGCAAAGGGGGCUCAGGCCUCGCCGCCUCCCAUAGCUCCUUACCCCAGCCCUACACGAAAGGACCUGCUUCUCCACAUGCAAGAGCUCUGCGAGGGGAUGAAGCUGCUGGCAUCUGACCUCCUGGACAACAACCGCAUCAUCGAACGGCUAAAUAGAGUCCCAGCACCUCCUGAUGUCUGAGCUCCAUGGGGCACAUGAGGCAUCCUGAAGCAUUAGAAUGAUUCCAACACUGCUCUUCUGCACCAUGAGACCAACCCAGGGCAAGAUCCCAUCCCAUCACAUCAGCCUACCUCCCUCCUGGCUGCUGGCCAGGAUGUCGCCAGCAUUACCUUCCACUGCCUUUCUCCCUGGGAAGCAGCACAGCUGAGACUGGGCACCAGGCCACCUCUGUUGGGACCCACAGGAAAGAGUGUGGCAGCAACUGCCUGGCUGACCUUUCUAUCUUCUCUAGGCUCAGGUACUGCUCCUCCAUGCCCAUGGCUGGGCCGUGGGGAGAAGAAGCUCUCAUACGCCUUCCCACUCCCUCUGGUUUAUAGGACUUCACUCCCUAGCCAACAGGAGAGGAGGCCUCCUGGGGUUUCCCCAGGGCAGUAGGUCAAACGACCUCAUCACAGUCUUCCUUCCUCUUCAAGCGUUUCAUGUUGAACACAGCUCUCUCCGCUCCCUUGUGAUUUCUGAGGGUCACCACUGCCAGCCUCAGGCAACAUAGAGAGCCUCCUGUUCUUUCUAUGCUUGGUCUGACUGAGCCUAAAGUUGAGAAAAUGGGUGGCCAAGGCCAGUGCCAGUGUCUUGGGGCCCCUUUGGCUCUCCCUCACUCUCUGAGGCUCCAGCUGGUCCUGGGACAUGCAGCCAGGACUGUGAGUCUGGGCAGGUCCAAGGCCUGCACCUUCAAGAAGUGGAAUAAAUGUGGCCUUUGCUUCUGUU